AAACUAACCCCUCUUUUUCUCCAAAGGAGUGCUUGUGGAGAUCGGAUCUUUUCUCCAGCAAUUGGGGGAAAGAAGGCUUUUUCUCUGAAUUAGCUUAGUGUAACCAGCGGCGUAUAUUUUUUAGGCGCCUUUUCGAAAACCUAGUAGUUAAUAUUCAUUUGUUUAAAUCUUAUUUUAUUUUUAAGCUCAAACUGCUUAAGAAUACCUUAAUUCCUUAAAGUGAAAUAAUUUUUUGCAAAGGGGUUUCCUCGAUUUGGAGCUUUUUUUUUCUUCCACCGUCAUUUCUAACUCUUAAAACCAACUCAGUUCCAUCAUGGUGAUGUUCAAGAAGAUCAAGUCUUUUGAGGUGGUCUUUAACGACCCUGAAAAGGUGUACGGCAGUGGCGAGAAGGUGGCUGGCCGGGUGAUAGUGGAGGUGUGUGAAGUUACUCGUGUCAAAGCCGUUAGGAUCCUGGCUUGCGGAGUGGCUAAAGUGCUUUGGAUGCAGGGAUCCCAGCAGUGCAAACAGACUUCGGAGUACCUGCGCUAUGAAGACACGCUUCUUCUGGAAGACCAGCCAACAGGUGAGAAUGAGAUGGUGAUCAUGAGACCUGGAAACAAAUAUGAGUACAAGUUCGGCUUUGAGCUUCCUCAGGGGCCUCUGGGAACAUCCUUCAAAGGAAAAUAUGGGUGUGUAGACUACUGGGUGAAGGCUUUUCUUGACCGCCCGAGCCAGCCAACUCAAGAGACAAAGAAAAACUUUGAAGUAGUGGAUCUGGUGGAUGUCAAUACCCCUGAUUUAAUGGCACCUGUGUCUGCUAAAAAAGAAAAGAAAGUUUCCUGCAUGUUCAUUCCUGAUGGGCGGGUGUCUGUCUCUGCUCGAAUUGACAGAAAAGGAUUCUGUGAAGGUGAUGAGAUUUCCAUCCAUGCUGACUUUGAGAAUACAUGUUCCCGAAUUGUGGUCCCCAAAGCUGCCAUUGUGGCCCGCCACACUUACCUUGCCAAUGGCCAGACCAAGGUGCUGACUCAGAAGUUGUCAUCAGUCAGAGGCAAUCAUAUUAUCUCAGGGACAUGCGCAUCAUGGCGUGGCAAGAGCCUUCGGGUUCAGAAGAUCAGGCCUUCUAUCCUGGGCUGCAACAUCCUUCGAGUUGAAUAUUCCUUACUGAUCUAUGUUAGCGUUCCUGGAUCCAAGAAGGUCAUCCUUGACCUGCCCCUGGUAAUUGGCAGCAGAUCAGGUCUAAGCAGCAGAACAUCCAGCAUGGCCAGCCGAACCAGCUCUGAGAUGAGUUGGGUAGAUCUGAACAUCCCUGAUACCCCAGAAGCUCCUCCCUGCUAUAUGGAUGUCAUUCCUGAAGAUCACCGAUUGGAGAGCCCAACCACUCCUCUGCUAGAUGACAUGGAUGGCUCUCAAGACAGCCCUAUCUUUAUGUAUGCCCCUGAGUUCAAGUUCAUGCCACCACCGACUUAUACUGAGGUGGAUCCCUGCAUCCUCAACAACAAUGUGCAGUGAGCAUGUGGAAGAAAAGAAGCAGCUUUACCUACUUGUUUCUUUUUGUCUCUCUUCCUGGACACUCACUUUUUCAGAGACUCAACAGUCUCUGCAAUGGAGUGUGGGUCCACCUUAGCCUCUGACUUCCUAAUGUAGGAGGUGGUCAGCAGGCAAUCUCCUGGGCCUUAAAGGAUGCGGACUCAUCCUCAGCCAGCGCCCAUGUUGUGAUACAGGGGUGUUUGUUGGAUGGGUUUAAAAAUAACUAGAAAAACUCAGGCCCAUCCAUUUUCUCAGAUCUCCUUGAAAAUUGAGGCCUUUUCGAUAGUUUCGGGUCAGGUAAAAAUGGCCUCCUGGCGUAAGCUUUUCAAGGUUUUUUGGAGGCUUUUUGUAAAUUGUGAUAGGAACUUUGGACCUUGAACUUACGUAUCAUGUGGAGAAGAGCCAAUUUAACAAACUAGGAAGAUGAAAAGGGAAAUUGUGGCCAAAACUUUGGGAAAAGGAGGUUCUUAAAAUCAGUGUUUCCCCUUUGUGCACUUGUAGAAAAAAAAGAAAAACCUUCUAGAGCUGAUUUGAUGGACAAUGGAGAGAGCUUUCCCUGUGAUUAUAAAAAAGGAAGCUAGCUGCUCUACGGUCAUCUUUGCUUAGAGUAUACUUUAACCUGGCUUUUAAAGCAGUAGUAACUGCCCCACCAAAGGUCUUAAAAGCCAUUUUUGGAGCCUAUUGCACUGUGUUCUCCUACUGCAAAUAUUUUCAUAUGGGAGGAUGGUUUUCUCUUCAUGUAAGUCCUUGGAAUUGAUUCUAAGGUGAUGUUCUUAGCACUUUAAUUCCUGUCAAAUUUUUUGUUCUCCCCUUCUGCCAUCUUAAAUGUAAGCUGAAACUGGUCUACUGUGUCUCUAGGGUUAAGCCAAAAGACAAAAAAAAUUUUACUACUUUUGAGAUUGCCCCAAUGUACAGAAUUAUAUAAUUCUAACGCUUAAAUCAUGUGAAAGGGUUGCUGCUGUCAGCCUUGCCCACUGUGACUUCAAACCCAAGGAGGAACUCUUGAUCAAGAUGCCCAACCCUGUGAUCAGAACCUCCAAAUACUGCCAUGAGAAACUAGAGGGCAGGUCUUCAUAAAAGCCCUUUGAACCCCCUUCCUGCCCUGUGUUAGGAGAUAGGGAUAUUGGCCCCUCACUGCAGCUGCCAGCACUUGGUCAGUCACUCUCAGCCAUAGCACUUUGUUCACUGUCCUGUGUCAGAGCACUGAGCUCCACCCUUUUCUGAGAGUUAUUACAGCCAGAAAGUGUGGGCUGAAGAUGGUUGGUUUCAUGUUUUUGUAUUAUGUAUCUUUUUGUAUGGUAAAGACUAUAUUUUGUACUUAACCAGAUAUAUUUUUACCCCAGAUGGGGAUAUUCUUUGUAAAAAAUGAAAAUAAAGUUUUUUUAAUGGAAAAAAAAA